ACUCCUUCCCGCUGCCUGCGCUCAGACCCCCGGCAUCCUGGCCCCUGCCCAGCGCCCAGAGCCCCCGGUGGCCGCAUCGCACUCCCCGCGCUCCGCCUCUCAUUGUCCUGUCCUGUCCCCUCUUCUACGUCUCCUCUGCCCAUCCUCCCAUUUUCACAAGUCUGUCCGGGACCCUGUCUCCUUCGGCCUCCACCCCUGCUGCCAUCGCUCCUCCCUCUCCCCUUCUUCCUUUUCCCCUCCCUCAGCCUACUGCGCCGCCUACCCCGCCCCCAGCCUUGCUGCCCUUUGGCUUCUCCUGUCCCGCAUCAUUACCCCGGCCCACAGCCCCAUUUGCCUGCAGUCGCUGCCUUUGCUCCUGAGAAGGAAUGCUGCCUGCUGCUUUGCCCAGAGUUGGCCCUGAGUGUUCCUAUCAGGCCCCGUUCACUCUGGGGUGGAUUAAACCACCUCCUGGAGGGUGCUGUAUCCCCACUGUGCAAUGGGGGUUUGUGCUGUGUGCAUUCCUGCCUGGUCCUUGAGAGUUGCUGACAGGUGGAACCUGAGGCAGCAGGACAGCCUGGCAUUGGCCACGGGACAUCGGCCACAACCAUAGCAACUUCGGCAUCAAAUGGGGCAGGAGAGAGAACAUUAAGAUUGAAGAAACUGAGGCUCAAAGAAGUUAGGGGUCCACCUGUGAGUACAUGCACAGGAAGGGGAAGAGCCCCCAUUGGAAGCAGAGCCCUGCCCCUUCCUCCUCACCCCUGGCUCCCUGGGAGGCCCCUCCUCUGGCCCAGUCCACAGCACUGUGACAGGCAGUGUGGAAGCCUCUUUCCCCCAGUACUCCCCUCAGAGCCCUUCCUUCCUUCUGAGCUGGGAAGGCCAGGUUGUAGUUAGCCAGGCCAAUCCAUUGGGGUUCUGAAUUAGCCACUUUCAGCUGUGUGUUCUUUGACAUUUCUGAGCUGCUCCAGGCCUCAGUUUUGUCACCUGCCACUUGUGGAGGGGGAAUGGGGAAGGGAACCAAUAGAUACAUAGCCCACACGGGGGUCUCUGGGUGAUGACUAGCCCUGGGUGCUGGGCAGCCCUCUGGUGAGACAGGCACAGUGGGAUGCUCAUUGCUCAUGGCUUCUCAGUGGGUCUUGGUGGGGGUCUGAGGACCUCAUUCCACCUGUCUCCUCAGGGGCCAGAGGCUGCUGGCCUGGCUGUUUAUGGCCCCCCUCCCUGGGAGGGUGGUGGGGUUUGGCCAGAGGCUGUGUGGAUGUCCAGAUGGGGCCUCCCUGGGGUCUUGGACCUGCAACUGAGUGGUUGUCUCCCUGCCAGGGGCUGGCAGUGACCACAGCUGUCCCAGUCAGGAGGAACACCUCCUGCCCUCCUCAUUCUUGCAGCCUCAGGAGCUGCUAAGAAGCAUGUUGGGCAGGUGGAGAUCCACUCAGUGACUUGUUCCAUGGCAUGUCAUGAGCACGAUUGGCAGGGCCAGGCCAGAUCAGUAAAAAGGGUGAGAGCUGCGAGGCAUAGGCCUGCUCAGUGCUCGAAGGGGAGAGGAGCUCAGCUGCCCCACAGGUGUGUGCCCUUGGGGGUCACUGAGCCUCUCUGAGCUUAUGGAAUUCUCCUGUCUGUAGAAUGGAGAUAAUGACUGUCUCAAGAGGUUGCUUGCACAGUUAUAUGAGACAAUGUAUGCAAAGGAUGUGGCACGUGUCUGGCCCUUGGCGAGUGAUCAGGCCCUGGCAGCUGUUAUUAUCAUCGCUGUUACGGGCUUUAUUGCCCUCCUUUGUUUGUAUGUCCAUCUUAGAGCUCAUUGAGGGCAGGGUCUGGGUCAGAUUUCUCUCUUGGCUACUCCUCCUCUUCCUGAUCCUCCCAGGGACAAGUCUGGCUUCAGCCCCGUGAAGCAGCUGGGAUGGGACAUCCUUACCAGGCCGGGGCUGUGUUCAGAGCUGCACAGUCCUGUACGGUAGCCAUUAGCCUCAUGUGGCCAGUUAGAUUCAAAUAAAACUUAAACAUUCAGUGUCUCAGUUGCAGUAGCCCCCUGCUGAGUGCUUGGUACCCACAUGCCAUUGGUGCCUACCUAUUGGACAGCACAGGGUAGAAUCUUUCCAUCAUCGCAGGAAGUUGUGCAGAGCUGGAGUCUCAGGGACUACAGCACCAGUAUCAUCCUCACUGUGGCUCAGCAGCCACCAGCCAUCUCCUGAGUGCUGGGCUGCCAGGACAUUUGUAAUUACACAGAAACCGAGUCCCACAGCCCUUCCCGAAUUUCCUCUCGGGUAGCCUUGCUCACCUGGUCGGGGAGGUUGUUGCCUGGAAGUCUUUAUCAGCCUAGGCUGGGAGGGCAGGGCUGGGAUUGCCCAAAUGCAGCUGCUGCCUCCUGUCCCCACCCUGUUUCUCCCACCUCUCCUGCCUGGCAAGGAGUCCCAGAGUGAUCUCCCUAAUUCACUGCUGUGGCCAGGGCCGAGGUGGCCCAGACACUUUGACCCCACUGCUCCCCUCAUAUGCUCUGGACACAUGGCCUCUUUCCUCCUGCCCACUCCGCUCUCCACCUGAACACCUUCUUGCUUCUCUCACUCCAGGCCUGACUUACGUGGCUGGUCCUCCAGGAAGCCUUUUCUCAUCUCUCACCCUCCGUGAGCUCUCCUGCCUUGGUGGUGCCCUCCCUCAGACCCCAUUUUUGGCACUCAGUGCCCUCCUCUGUGGGUGUGUUCUUGUAUUUGCUUGUUCUCUUGGUCAGGCACACAGCAGAUAAUCCUCUGAGUGCCGACGACACAUCAGGGGUACAGAAAGGUCUGAAUGAAUCCCAUGUUCCCUAGCCCUACAGCUGGGCACGCAGUAGGGGCUCAGGAGAUGCUGUGGAAUCAAUGACCAGAUGCUGAAUGAGUCCCUCAUGGAAAAAGCUGAUGCAUGGGGCCUCUCCUUGCCCCUGGAGCUAGAGGCAGCCAUGAGCUCCAGCCGCCCCGAGCCGGGUCCCUGGGCACCCCUGAGCCCCCGCCUUCAGCCCCUGUCCCAGAGCUCUUCCAGCCUGCUGGGUGAAGGCCGGGAACAGAGGCCAGAGCUCCGCAAGACUGCCAGCAGCACCGUGUGGCAGGCCCAGCUGGGCGAGGCCAGCACCAGACCCCAGGCCCCGGAGGAAGAGGGGAACCCGCCUGAGAGCAUGAAGCCAGCACGGGCCUCUGGCCCCAAGGCGCGACCCAGUGCUGGAGGCCACUGGUGGAGCAGCACUGUGGGCAAUGUGUCCACCAUGGGCGGCAGUGACCUGUGUCGCCUGCGGGCCCCUAGUGCUGCUGCUAUGCAGAGGAGCCAUUCAGACCUGGUCCGUAGCACCCAGAUGCGGGGACACAGUGGUGCUCGGAAGGCCAGUCUCAGCUGCUCAGCCCUUGGCAGCAGCCCUGUCCACAGGGCUCAGCUGCAGCCAGGUGGUACUUCUGGCCAGGGUGGCCAGGCCCCUGCAGGCCUGGAAAGGGACCUGGCUCCUGAGGAUGAGACUUCUAACUCAGCCUGGAUGCUGGGGGCGAGUCAGUUGUCAGUGCCACCACUAGACCUGGGGGACACAACUGCCCACAGCAGCAGUGCCCAGGCUGAGCCCAAAGCUGCUGAACAGCUGGCUACCACCACCUGCCAUGCUCUGCCCCCAGCUGCUCUACUCUGUGGCAUGAGGGAGGUGAGGGCUGGUGGCUGCUGCCAUGCCCUACCUGCCACAGGGAUCCUGGCCUUUCCCAAACUAGUGGCGUCAGUGAGCGAGUCUGGGCUGCAGGCUCAGCAUGGGGUGAAGAUCCACUGUAGGUUGUCUGGGGGGCUCCCUGGGCAUUCCCAUUGCUGUGCCCACCUUUGGGGUCCCGCUGGGUUAGUCCCAGAGCCUGGCUCUAGGACCAAAGAUGUGUGGACCAUGACCUCAGCCAAUGACUUGGCCCCUGCAGAGGCAUCCCCGCUGUCAGCCCAGGAUGCUGGUGUGCAGGCGGCCCCAGUGGCGGCCUGCAAGGCUGUGGCCACCAGUCCGUCCCUGGAAGCGCCUGCAGCCCUGCAUGUGUUCCCAGAGGUAACUCUGGGGUCCAGCCUGGAGGAGGUGCCGUCCCCUGUGCGGGAUGUGCGAUGGGAUGCUGAGGGCAUGACAUGGGAGGUGUACGGAGCUGCGGUGGACCUGGAGGUGCUCGGUGUGGCCAUCCAGAAGCACCUGGAGAUGCAGUUUGAGCAGCUGCAGCGGGCGCCCGCCAGCGAGGACAGCCUGUCUGUGGAGGGCCGGAGGGGGCCACUGCGGGCUGUCAUGCAGUCCCUGCGGCGCCCCAGCUGCUGCGGCUGCUCCGGCGCGGCCCCCGAGUGAGGAGCUGUGGCCCUUGGAGCUGGCCUGGGCCCACUGACUUAGUCCUAGACCUGGGCCAGGGACGGUGGGGGCUCCGUGCCCCCUGGACCCACCGGCAGCUGGGCACAUCUCUCACCUGAAUAUUGGCUGCCUCCAGACCACAGGACUGCAGCCUGGGGCUUCCGGCCCUACACAGCUGGGCUGUUUUCUUAAGGGCUUGAUUUCCAAGGGCCACAUCUCUGCACCUUCCGGGCUCUGAACUUUGAGACAGGGCUUUAGCACUGUGCAGAGGGGAGAUCCUGAGUUUUCUGUAAAAAAUGACCUUUUGUUCACUCCACCCUCAGAACUCUGCCAUGUUGCCUCGUCAGACUCUUGGUGGCUUUAUUUGAAAUCAGUGCUGAGAAAUAGUGAAUUCUCGACAUGAAAUGUGAGGCCCCAGUGACAGGGACUGCCCAGGUCUUUAGGGAAGGGGACUGAUGUUAUCAGAGGCCUCCUGUGUGCCACAUACUGUGCUUGUCCUGUCUUCACCUCUUCAUCCUGGCAAGCCUUCAUUUGGCAAGGCUGUAGCCGAUGUGCCCCACGCUGGACAGCUUGAAGAGGUGGGACUGAGAUCCAAAGCCAGGGCCAGCUGAGCCGUGGGUGUUGCCCUGUAGCAUGUGCCCGGUCCAGUCAGUGCAGUCAUGUAUGAGGAGAAUUUACUGAGCUCAUACUCUGUGCUGGGUUCUGUGGAUUCUGUGGUGAAUGAGACAGAGGCUGCCCCUGCCCUGGCUGAGCUCAUGGUGUGGGUUGGGGAUGGCAGGGGAGGAUGCUGACCAUUACGGAGGGCUGCCAGGCUUCCAGGGUCAUUGUGUCAGAGGCUGGCCUGAGGAAGGGGAGAAUGGGUGGCCACCUGCCCUAAUCUCAGUUACAAAGCCUAAAAUUGCACUAUUUUCACCUCAUUCUGUCGGCUGAAGGAUUUCUCCCCAGCUGGUGCAGUUUGUGGAAGGAGGGAGGGCAGGAAUGGAGGGGGACAGGGCAGGAGUUUGCCCUGGCCCUGGGGUAGGGGCUGUGAGGCUGUGGGGGCUCGCUUGCCCACAUGACCUGACCUAGGCUAGGCAGUGGGGGCCAGGGGCCUUGGAGAGACAGAAACAUGGGCUUUGGCACAGUCUGACUUCAUUGCCCAAAGAUUUCUCGAGGCCUGUGAAGAAUGGGAGUGGGCUUGUGUUCUUGUCCUGGGUCUUUGUCUUGAAGAUCCUAAGAUCCCGUGACACAGCCCCCCAAUCCACCCGUGUGAGGGACCAGAGGGCUAGUGUGGGGUCAUGGCCCACGACCUGGCCUGUUUCUGGAGCCUCUUCUGCACCUAGGAGCCCAGGACCCCCACAGUGGUGGCUUACUUUUCCCCAUCCUCAAGGACCUGGUACUCAUUGAGGUGGAAAUGACUCAUGCAACAGUUGGUGAAUUUGUAAAGCAGGAGUGGCAUUUCAACAGGCCACAAGGACAAAGUGACAAAGGCGUGCGUCAGGUCAGAUGCCUCCUGAAGCCCAACGAUGGACCAUUCUCACCCGUAAACAUGCCUUUCCCAUAUGCAUAGGUGCACCCCUUGGGAUUCUGGGGCUGUCAGUCCCUUUGUGUAUGGUGCCAGGGCAGGCAGCUCACGUUCUGGGGAGUGACACAUGGGUAUAUGCCAUCUUCAUGCCUGGCUCCCCAUGGAGUCUCCAGGAACCCCAGCCUGUUAGGGCCACAUGAGAGAGAACAAAUGGCUGUGGGUGCAUGGGGAGGGACCUUUCACACAGGGCCAUAGCUAAGUAGGGUCUUGAGGAUGCAGGGGUUAGACAGGUGGGUGGAGAGAGGGCAGGACCUGCCUGGCAGAUGGAACAGCCUGGUCAGAUACUUGGAUGUGCCUGUCCUGCCUGGGCCAUAAUGAGUUUCUGCAGUGGCGGCUCAUUUGGAGCGUUUGUUGGGUUGGGAGGUGACCAGGGGUCCCCAUUGUGAAGAUCCUGAUGUAAAUGAGGAAAGGAACUUUAAGGGAACUGUGGAAGGGGUUCUGAGGUGGGACCAGAUUUCAGUUUAGAAAUAUCCAUUUGGCUUCCAGUGGAGAUGUGCCAGGUGACACCAAGGAGGGGCCUGUUUAGGGGCAAUGGAGUGGGCAGCUGGGGGCUGGGUUCAUACACGUGCACACACACGCAUACACAGGCACACAUGUGUGCAAUGGAUUUGGGGAGGAGGCAUUUCAGGAUGCUGAGGUUUCCAGUUUGAGCAAGAGGAGGGUGAGGCCACUACCUGGGUCAAGGUGAAUGGCAUGUUCAGCAGGUGCAGAAAGGGCCACCUGCCACAGGGUUUGGCUGGGACCAGUGAAACCUACUUCAUGAAGAGACUUUCUUCUGUGUCACGUGCAGAUUCUUAUGCAUUCACGCUGGCUGGGUGCCACUCUGUGCUACCUCCAUGCUGCCCUGGCUUGCCAGGAUGGCAGGCCGGGCUGGGCUCAGCCAAGCUCCCACUCACCUCAUCGUCACUGAGAUGAGUAUUUGCAGAGCGGUGCUGAAAUCCAACACCUGUGUCUUGGCUGGGGCCCCAGAUGAUUCUCCUGGCUAAACCACGAUCCUUGUCUCCCUAGCCCAGUUGCACAGCUGCUGCUGACAGGUCUACCUGAAGUGACUGCAGCCUCAUUUCUGAUUGGAACUGGAGACCCCUCCCAACCCCCUUUGCUGUGCCCUCUCCUGGAACAGCCCUGAUGCCUGCAGUGGUUUAGGGCCCCAGAGCAUGGCCAGCGGUUUAGUUUACAGAUCUCCUCCCCUUGGACUCUAGAUUUCUGGCCAGACUUUCUGGGUCCCUUUCAGGCCCUGCUCUGGGAGGUGUUGGAGUUCACUGUUGAUGUGUUUGUUUGGCUUUGAAUUCAAAACAGAUACAAAUUUGGAGGUGAGAGCUUUGCCAGACCCCAGCAGGGAUGGGGCAUCGGUCCUGACUGGUCUUGUUUAUUUUGUCCUGGUAAAUUCUGUUCUUUGGAGCAUAAACCCUGGAGUCCUAGAGCCCCUUGCCUCAGCAGGAAUCCCCCCUCUGUCUGCUCCAGGGGCUCCCUGCUUCUGCCCACCUGCUCUCCUUCCAUGGCAUUCAGGACCCCCGACAGCUGAAGCCUCUCUUCAUAUAGCUUGUCCCCUCUGGGCCUGCCUGUCUUGUGUCCAGGACACAAGACACGCAUCCCUUGUCUGGCCCCAGGCUGCCAUCACUGUCACAAGAAACUCAUAGAGUAGAGCUGGUCUGAGGUCACAGUGCUGGUGGUGGUGGAAAAGCAGGGAUGGCCUGUUCCACUGUGAUCUUACCUCCUGUGUCACCUGGAUUGGGUCUCUGUCCCCUUAGACAUGCUAGAUCCUAACUUUACAAGGGCUGAAGGGGUCUUCUACACGCAGGUCCCAACACUUUGGGCUGGGGUUGGCCACCGUAGCUUAGUGGGCUAAAGCUGGAGUUUGAAUCUGGAUAUAUAGGAUCCACACCUAUAGCCAUGUGAUCUUGGGCAAGUUACAAGCCUUGAUCAUCUUCCUCAUCUGUAAGAUGGGGAUGACAAUGGUGCCUCCUUCACAUGCUUGGUGUGGAGAUUAAAUAGAAUAACCCAAGUAGUGCCUGGCACUGAGUUAGUGCUCAGCACACAGGCUGGUAGUGUUGGGCACCCCUCUCAUAGCCACAUUCAGGGGCCACCUCUUACCCUGCCAGCUUGGCUGUGAUCACAGCCCACAUCCCACUUCCUUAAAAGUCCCUUGUUCAGAGCCUCUUUCCAGGUUCCUCGCCCCACAGCUUUGCACCCUGCCUGGGACUUGGCCCUCUGGCUGGGGCUUCUGAAAAUGUAGUUCCCAGAGUGCAUUGAGGAGGGCUACCCUAGCCCUCACCACUCAUCUUGGGCUGGGUUCCCCAGAAGCUUCUGCUGAGAUGAGGAUGCUGGAGUUAUUAGGGAGGGGAGAGCAAGUUAAGGGAGGGGCAGAAGGCAAGGCAGGGUGUGAUUUCAGUCCAAGUCAGACCCUAAAGGGGAGCCCUGGAUGCAGUCCCACCUCAGAGUAAGGACUACCCAGGGGUGAAGAUGUAGCCUCCAGGCACUUCUGCUCUCUGGCAGGCAGGCUAGGAAGCUCUAGGAGCCCCAGGGUAGGUUUCUGCUGGAGUCGUAGGGCCUAUUUUGGGGGAAGUUGUGCACAGAAACCACCAGAGGGAGUCACAGGCAUCUGGGGGUGCACCCAUUGACAUUUGCAUCCAUGUCAUGCCAAGCUUGUAGCCCACAAAUGCCCAACCCUUUUCUCCAUGCAUUGCUCUGUCUCAGUUUUGUUCACGCCAAGCAGCCUUGGUUAGUUAAAUGCAGAGCUUGGCAUUUGCCCAUGUUAAAUUCCUUCUCCUUUUUCAUUCUGGCCUGGCCUGGUUUUGCCAUCUGAAGCUAUGACAAGUCCUUUAUCAGUUUUCAUCCAACUUGUCAGGCAGGGCAGGGCUGGUAUGAAGCCCAGGACAUAUCACUGGGACAUCCCAUAGGUCUGUGAGAUUCCCAGGUCCCUCCAAAUCCACACGGUCAUCAUGGGCAAAUUAGUUUAAGUCUGAUCUGUUAAGAUCCAGAUCUCUCACACCAACAGCACACACCCCUUUUUCCCAUGGCCAUGGAAGGAGGGUAGCAUAGCCUGACUCGAGUCCUCGUUCUCAGCAGAACUGGUUCUGUGGUGGCCACUUCCCUUUCUCAACUUUUACCUACUUCUGUUUAAUAGGUUGUUCUGCAAGUCUGAGAGCAACAGCAAGCUUAGAAGUGUGGACUCAGCCUGGUACAGUGGCUCAUGCCUGUAAUCCCAGCACUUUGGGAGGCUGAGGUGGGCUGACUGCUUGAGCUCAGGAGUUCGAAACCAGCUUGGGCAGCAUGGAGAAAUCCCAUCUCUACAAAAAAUACAAAAAUUAGCUGGGCAUGGUGGUGUGCAUCUGUAGCCUCAGCUACUCAGGGGGUUGAGGUGGGAAGAUGGCUUGAGCCCAGGAGGUGGAGGUUGCAGUGAGCCGAGAUAGUGCCACUGUGCUCCAGCCUGGAUGACGGAGCCAGACCCUGUUUCAAAAAAAGAAAAAGACAAGAAAGAAGUAUGGACUCUACCUUCUUGCCCUUGUGGAGAUUGGGAACUGCCUGCCCUUGGCCUCUUUCCUGUCCAUCUUGUAUUAUGAAAGGCUGUUUCUGGCACACCCGGGCUCCUCUGUGUGGUUUCUGGGAAGUGACUGAGGGUCAGGGGAAUGGAGCCCCUCUGCAGCCGGCCGCUGGUACCUUCCCUAUUGAACCCUUCUUUAGGUUUGCUCACUCUUUUUGAUGGGUGUCUUUCCAAAGCUGGCUGGGGACCUCCCUGAUUGAGAGACAUGGGGCCAGUUCUGUUGCUGUGGCUACACGGGAAUAAUAAAGCAGAAGAACACCUGAGGAAAGCUGAUGUUUACUAAAAAAAAAAACAAGCGAAACCAAAGUGACGUGGGCCCAUAGGAUUGGGGAUGGGUGGUGGGGUCUGACUGCCUUGUCCCAAGAGUUGGGUGAAUGCCGCCUUUGCUCACUUGUGCGGUCACUCUCCAGGACUCCUGCCUGGCUUCUCCCACUCCAAGCCCGAGAUAGCCCAGCAAGGAGGAAGGUCUGGCCCCAAAAUACGAGCUCCCCAAGUGGAUAUCCUAAAAUUCAUCUUUCAUGGCCCUACUUUAUUGGGAGGGAAUGUGAAAAUUGUGGGAAUAUGUCCAUUGACAUCUGGGGCUCAGGGCAGGGGAGUGUGUCUAGUUUUAAGGUGUGCGCUUUUAGCCAUGCAGUCAUCGCCCAGUCUGUCCUGCCUGGAGCUUUUCAUUUCCCUGCAGCUUUCCUGAGAAAAGACAGAGUGUGCUUUCUCUGCAUCCUAUGAACAUGGCCCCAGGACUGCAGCACCUCUGUGUGCACACAGCCAAGGACAGUCGGGGGACCUCUGCUGGUCCUGCACCCGCUGCCCUGGGUGCUCUGUCAUCCCCAUCCCCCAUUUCUCUUUAAUCUGUUCUUCUUUUGUGGUUUCAUGUUCUCUUUGUUCUGGGUUAUUCAGAACCUGUCUGCCUCCCCACUGUCCAUUGUACUUGUUCCUGCCUCCUCCUGCUUUGUGCCAAGGAUUUACUUGCCUUCGCCUUCUGGCUCCAUACAGUAGUCUCUCUUCUUGCGGUCUUGGCCAUUCCCCCCACCAGGCCCCCAGCUGUGGCUGUGUCUGGGUCUUGGCAUUUGUGAUUUACAUGGGUCUAGGCCCUUUCUCUCCACCUGUCCUUCCCCUCUUUGGACACAAACCAAAACAUCUGAGCAUCUCCUUACAGAGGGAGGUCUCCCUGGGGUUGCUGUGCCAAGUUUCCAUUGCUUUUGCCCAGAAUGAGAAAUCAGUUGUCAGUGGCCCUGCUGGGUGAAUGGAAGGACUUUGGUCGGGCUGGAAGGGCACCCCAUCAGUCCUAACUUUUGGUGGCCCUUGUUGGUGGCUGGCUGGCUAGGCUGCUAGAGAGGUACAUCAGGUGGGUGGCACCCAUCUGCUGGCUUUAGGCAGGCCAUCUCCUCAUCCAUGUUUUCAGAAUCUUCUUGCAUGGCUUGUAAUUGGGUUGGGGUGUGGCCUGAGCCCCUGUGGGGACACACUGCACUGUCCCACCUGUAUGCUUCUCUGCUGUCAGGAACUGGAUUCGUGUCCAAGAGCCAAGGCUAGGGACUGGAGGAGGAGAUUUCUGUCUUUGACCCCUCCAUAUUAGUCCAUUUUCAUGCUGCUAUAAAGAACUGCCUGAGACUGGGUAAUUUAUAAAGGAAAGAGGUUUAAUUGACUCACAGUUCCACGUGGCCCGGGGAGCCUCAGGAAACUUACAGGAAGCCUCAGGAAACUUACAAUCAUGGCAGACAGCGAAGGAGAAGCAAGGCACCUUCUUCACAAGGCAGCAGGAAGGAAAAUGAAUGCAGAAGGAACUACCAAACACUUAUAAAACCAUCAGAUCUCGUGAGAACUUACUAUCACAAGAACAGCAUGGGGGAACCGCCCCCACGAUUCCAUCACCUCCACCUGAUCUCUCCCUUGUCACAUGGGGAUUAUAGGGAUUACAAUUCAAGAUGAGAUUUUGGGUGGGGACACAGCCAAAGCAUAUCACCCUCCCAGGCCUGAGCAAGGCCCAAGCAGGGAGCCUCUGUUGGGGCUGGAACCCUGGGAGGGGUAGAAUUCUCCCCUCCACUCAGAUUUGUUCCCUGUUGCUGCCCACCUGGCCCCUGCCCUGCAGCCUUCUGCCUGGCCUUCUCUCUGUUCACUUCUCAUUUUUAGCAGUCAACAGACUGGGAGAUGGUGGCCAAGGGUGUCAUUUUGUACACAAGCUUUGUGGCUUUUGUAAGCCCAGCCUGCAACUCUUGAGGAAAACUCUUUGGUUUGAUUUUUUUUCUCUUCAGAGUUGGGGGUAUUCAGGGAGAUGGGCAAGGGCUUCUUGUGAAGAUUUCAAUUCUUGAAGGGGUGGAAGCCUCCUGGGCUGGGGGAAGGGGUGGGGCAGGAACCAGCAGGGGUGUGGACACAGGGGGCUGGCACCUGGGAUACCGUAGGACAGCUGGGCAGGAAGUCGGAUGCUGCUUUAUUGAAAUUUUUGAUAUUUUAUCAUUUUUUCAUUAGUUUUUAUUUUAAAACACUGCUUUAAAAUAAUUAAAAUAUGAUUUAUCUUGGUUACCGAA